GGCGGCUGCCGCGAUCUCUCCCUGGUAGCGGGAGGCUGAGCGGGCGGCGCGACGCGGGGGCCGACGGGGGCGCCGGGUGGCCGCGCCGGAAGUGCCUUGCGCGGCAGAGGAAGCGCAGGGACAGAGCGGAGCAGGCCGAGCCGGCGGAAAGGGUCUUUGCUGCUGCGCCCGGGCAGGGGCUGCCGCGGCCCCAGGUCCCGCUUCGAGACGCGGCGCGGUCCAGGCGGGAGGCGACUCCCUAGGAAGGGACCCGGGGCGGGAGGAGGAAGUGAGGCCGCGCGGAAGGAAGGCGGCGAGCCCCGGGGCCCCGAGGCCUUGGCCGCGUCACAGCACCCACAUGGCCUCUGGAGUGGGCGCGGCCUUCGAGGAACUGCCUCACGACGGCACGUGUGACGAGUGCGAGCCCGACGAGGCUCCGGGGGCCGAGGAAGUGUGCCGAGAAUGCGGCUUCUGCUACUGCCGCCGCCAUGCCGAGGCGCACAGGCAGAAGUUCCUCAGUCACCAUCUGGCCGAAUACGUCCACGGCUCCCAGGCCUGGACCCCGCCAGCUGACGGAGAGGGGGCGGGGAAGGAAGAAGCGGAGGUCAAGGUGGAGCAGGAGAGGGAGAUAGAAAGCGAGGCAGGGGAAGAGAGUGAGUCGGAGGAAGAGAGCGAGUCAGAGGAAGAGAGCGAGACAGAGGAAGAGAGUGAGGAUGAGAGCGAUGAGGAGAGUGAAGAAGACAGCGAGGAAGAAAUGGAGGAUGAGCAAGAAAGCGAGGCCGAAGAAGACAACCAAGAAGAAGGGGAAUCCGAGGCGGAGGGAGAAACUGAGGCAGAAAGUGAAUUUGACCCAGAAAUAGAAAUGGAAGCAGAGAGAGUGGCCAAGAGGAAGUGUCCGGACCAUGGGCUUGAUUUGAGUACCUAUUGCCAGGAAGAUAGGCAGCUCAUCUGUGUCCUGUGUCCAGUCAUUGGGGCUCACCAGGGCCACCAACUCUCCACCCUAGACGAAGCCUUUGAAGAAUUAAGAAGCAAAGACUCAGGUGGACUGAAGGCCGCUAUGAUCGAAUUGGUGGAAAGGUUGAAGUUCAAGAGCUCAGACCCUAAAGUAACUCGGGACCAAAUGAAGAUGUUUAUACAGCAGGAAUUUAAGAAAGUUCAGAAAGUGAUUGCUGAUGAGGAGCAGAAGGCCCUUCAUCUAGUGGACAUCCAAGAGGCAAUGGCCACAGCUCAUGUGACUGAGAUACUGGCAGACAUCCAAUCCCACAUGGAUAGGUUGAUGACUCAGAUGGCCCAAGCCAAGGAACAACUUGAUACCUCUAAUGAAUCAGCUGAGCCAAAGGCAGAGGGCGAUGAGGAAGGACCCAGUGGUGCCAGUGAAGAAGAGGACACAUGAAGGCUUGCUACCCCCAGUGGAAAAUCAUCCCCUCCCCUUGUGUGUAUGUGACAGCGUGUAUGUAACGGCUUCUGAUUUCUGUGAAAGCUGCUCAGCAACAAACGUACUUCCACCAGAUGUGUCCCCAGAUCCACAGCAGGCACAUAUCUCUCCAAGGGAUGACCAGUUUUAUGCUUACUGUGUGCUUCUCAUCCCCUGGUUGUGGUAGGUCAAGGAAAAGAGCCCCUUUGAUCCACCAGGAGCAAUUAAGAAAGGUCCUUCAGGUAAUCCCUCAAUGGCUGCUUUGAACUUACUCAGGAAAGCCAGCCCCCAUAAUAUUGUAUUACCAAACAGUAUCGCUUUGUUAGGAAGGAUCUGGAAUAAUCUUGAAGGGAAGUCAGAGUUUUCUCCCUGCCUAUUAACAAAAACCCAAUUUUGUUCAUAUUGAAGCAUGAAAUAAAUGAGAGCAAGGUAGGGCCAAAUUAACUCUUGUGGACAGUCCCUAAAAGUCCAGUUCUACAUUUGUGAAAAUUGUGGUGCCAUGAAUUAAGAUGGAUGACUGGAAAAAGGUGUUGGAGAAAGAGUUAAAGAUGAGGAAGAGAUAUUUUUAGUAUAUGAAGUUAUCCAGGACUUGAUAUUCAUAAUUCAGUGCUGUGGAAAUGAAAAAAAUGAUUGAAGAGGUGGAACGGAAAUGACCUUAGGGGGAAAAAAAAGGACCAAAGAAGUCUGAUUAAAAGUUGAAAUCAGUAUUUCUGAAUUCAAAUUGCUUGAAUUUCCAAAAUAGUCAGUAAAGGAUCUAAUAGAACCAGAAUUAUUUGGGUGAAUUCUGCAGGUUUUAUGGGCUUGUCACAACGUGAAGGGCUGGAAUGUAUAUUACCAAAUGGGAAUUUCCAUUGUAGGUUUUUGCUAGUCCCACCCCCAUUUUAGCCUAAUUUGGCUUAAACGCAGUAUGGGGAGAAUUGUUCCCAUUCCAUGUGUUCUGAAUUCAGCUCAUCUCCCAGCAUAUAGAUAUAUCCUCCUUUAACUCCGACCAGAACCCUUCUUCCUGUGGCACUCCCCACCCAUAGACCUUCAGAUCAUCUCCCACACCCUGGAUCUCACUCUCCUCUUAGUAACAGAGACACUCCUGAGGUUGGACUUCCUUGCUUUUCUCUACUUCCAAAUCACAAUUUCUUACAACCAAGCUUUGUGCUCCCGAGUAAGCAGGGAUGUACUAGGGGAAUGUAAAACUGCAAACUUAAAAACCUGCAUCUUCUUGAAGCAUCAGUUUUACUUACCAAAUGGUUUAGAGUCAUAAGAUGACCUAUUUUUAUAUAAAAGUUAUAUUAUAGAAUAAAAUGUUCAUACGCAUAGACUGUUAAGAUAAAAAAAUAGGAAUCUUGCAAGGUAAUUCUUAUUUGCAAGUGGGUUAUGUGUUCACUCUCCUCUACCUUUAUGGUAUUUUGGUGUUCACUUACGAAGCAUACAACUAGAACCAUAUCCAAGCAGACUCUGGGUUGCUGUUAACCCAGGGCCUAGACUUCUAGUGCCUCUGAGGCAGAACCAAAGGAGCCUGCACUGGGGGAAAUCCCUUUUCCUGCCUGCCUGUCUGCCUGUGACCUGUGUACGUAUUACAGGCUUUAGGACCAGCUGAUUGUUAUGCUUGCAGGAUGGUUUUGAAACAGAAACAAUACUUGUUUACUGUAGGAAUCCUAUUUAUAUUAUUUUUCAGUCCUGUGAAUGCUGUGAAAAGAUUUAUUCCUUUGAGGCCAGGAAGCUCCCAGGCAUAUAUGCUUCUAGGUUAGGAUUGUCCUGACUCACUAAAGAUGCCAGGAUAUUGGGGCUGAGGGGAGUUUGAGGUGUUAAAAAAAAAAAAAAAAAAGCAUUUUUCUCUCAAACUGAUGGCCAAGAAAUGGCUAGGACAAUUUUGGUGCUUUACCUAUCUCUGCAAAGACUGGAGAAUUUGGCAUACCAUUAAUUACAACCACCAAUCAUAUCCAACAAAAGUACCCUAAAAGAAGGACCAGUGGCCACUCUCGAAAAAAUUUAAGUAUCAGAAGAUUAAAAAGAUUUUAGGAUUUGGAAGCUUGUAUUGUCUUUCCCCAAUAAUCAUUGUUUGAUCUCCAAAUAGUAGCCUUAUAUUAGCAAUAGACAGAUCAUUGGUUCUCCAUAUCUGAUCAUAUGUUACUACUUUGAAUCAGUAUUUGGGAAAUUCAAGCAUUUAUGCAGUGGAUAUAAAUGGAAAUAUAAAAAUAUUUGCCAACCUGUCUCAGUAACUUAUCAUAUCUCUGUGAUCCUCAAGGAAAGCACUUUUGCUUUUACUUAGAAAGCGUUUCAGAUUUGCUUUAUAGACUCCUGCUGUCUUCAGUACCUGAUAAAACUUUAACCAGGGAAGCAUUAAACACAGUGCAGCAGCUUUUGCCCAGGCUUCUAAGUUCCUGCCGGCAGCAUUUAUCAAUGUAAGAACUAGGAUGCUUCCUGCAGUGGCACUACCUUCCCCUAGAGCUGGAGCAUGCUGCUUGGCCUUAAGCCCCAGCAUGAUGAGGCUUCCCUCCUGCCAGGUCAGUAAAAGUUAGAGAGCUCAGAAUUGGGUCUUGCCUGGGUGCAGGUGGCAGGGUUUGCUGAAACCCCUAAAGAGAAGUCACCAAGGGAGGCAGGUAAUGAAUGUUUCCAGAAUCAGUCGGAUACUCAUAGCAAUUUCUGGCUAUCUUUCAAAUGUUGAAUUUCUGGAUGCUGAGAGGGACUUUGAUUUGAUAUCAUUAAAUCCAGGACAGUCCCAAGAAGUGCUUGGAGUCUCGGCUCUGACAGCCCAAGAAGGGAAAUAACUUGUAUUAAGGAACAACUAUGAGCCAGGCCCUGAGCUGUCUCUUAGAUAAUAAAACAGAUGGGGAGUGGAAGAGUCAUUUGCUUCAAGUUAUACAGCUAGGAAAUACUCAAGCCAAAUCUUGAACGCAGCUCCCCCUAAUUCUGUGGACAGGCACUUUGUACCACACACCAUGGUCCACCUAAAAACAGAAGGAUAAAAAGACUUCAGGUUUUCCCACUGUGUGCUGACCAUCCCAAUUUAUGAAUCUUCUUCAAAAUGACAUUUCACAGUUAUAGUUAGGGCUCAGAAAUGGCAUUGAGGUAGCCUUAUUUCUCCCCUUUAGCAGAUGCUUUAAGUACACAUUGCUGACUUGAGCCCACCCCCAGGAGUUAGGAGAACAUUUCCUUUUUCAUGCCAUCUUCCAUAAAUAAGGUGUUUCUUGGCCUUCAAAGAUAUAGAACUUUGCAGCAGUAGUAAAAGUGAAGGGUGUUCUGCUCUCUACUCAACUUUAUUUGAAAAUGUCUGCAGCUUCACUCCUGUAGAAAAGGAAAUCUUCAUAUUUUAGUAAACUUAGCCGCCAGUGUACUCUGUGAGGAUGUGGCAAUUCAAAGUCCAGUGAAUCUGGACUCUCUUACUGAUUCCUGGUUUUAGUGUGUGUGUCGGGGGAGUGUGUACCUAUAUAUAAAGGACAAGUGUGAUAUGUGUGUAUAUGUAUAUACAUACAUACAUGUCCGCACACACACACACAAUAUUUGAGAGCUAAGGAAAACUCAAAGCAGCCCCUUCAUUAUCUUGCGUACUACUUCAAAGAUUUCUGUCAGCCCUAAUUACAAGUGUCACCAUAUAGUUGGGGCUUAGGUACUUGCUUACAGGAAGAGCAAUUCCCUAGCAAAGGUCAUUAGCUCCUAAGGCACUGAGUCAAAGUGACAGCCCUGAAGGAAAUUGCACUCCAGCCCUCCUCCAGGAUGUCUAAUAAGAUGGGAAACUUGGAUGCCCAGCCAUUUUGGUGACCUGAGAGUCUAACUACUCCAGUUAGACCUAAGGGCACAAAUGCAGAAUUCAUGACCUUGUAGUUGUGGCAGGGUCUAGGAAGUCCUCUCUCCCCAAGUAGAAAAUAUUCUCUUGCCAUUCCUGAAAUUCCACAUUCAUAUAAUGGCUGUGCAAUACAUGCUUCUCAAUAAGAAAAUUAACUGCACGUUUACUGUGUGCUGAUCACAUCAGAUUUUUAUGUUUAAAAAAAUCUCAUUAUGGAUUGAGUCCAGCCCAGCUCUAAGAGAAAAAGAAGGCCCAUAUGGGAGACUUCAGUCUCAUUAUUAUUGCCUUUAUCCAGCAGUGCUUAUGAAGCCCCCUACCCUGUCCCAUUCCAGAAACCAUAAGACUCAGGCAGUUCUUGAUUCUGGAGGCCUGCCUGGUAAGAUAAGAUAGUAUAAUUUGGAACUGAGAACAUACCAGAAACAGCAGAACGAGGGCCAGAGCAGAAAAAUGAAAAUAAGUGGAGACACUUAUGGAUACAUUGGUGCAAAAAAAGCCACGGAGCCCAUACUGGGCUUGAUAUGACUUUGAGGGGACAGCAGAUUAAUACUUAAUGAGGGUUAAACCUGACCAGUCUUUCUACAGUGACAGGCCACACUGCAUGAAUGGGGAGAACCAAUGAAUCCAUUGUCCUCUGCCUAUUUUCCUGUGCACAGUCACAUUCCCUCCUUAGGAAUCUUCCCCUUCCACCCUUUACAUUAAACAAGGGAACACUGAAUCUUUCAAGGGAAUUACACGUUUGGGUUAAUGUUUCAGUAUAUCAUUUUCAUACUGUAAAUUAUUUUGUAAGAGAGAUUUACUGCUAUCCCAGGAUGUUCGGACUUGGUGCCCCUGUGCAUUUGGAAAUCAAUAAACUAUUACUGGAAAUGCCAUUUGUCUCUCAGAGUUGUGCACAAAGGACCCUGCAAGGUGUAAAUAUUUAUGACGAGCUGCAUACUUGACUGUGGUAAUGCUGGAGAUGAUGGUGUUUUGGUUACUAGAUGUGGGAGUCUAAUUUACUCCUGACUUUUCCACAGUGCCUUAGGAGAGAGCUCUGGGAAGUGGCAAAAGAACAGACUUAAGAUCAUUAUUAUUUAGUGAUAAGUUUUCUCCUCAAAGUAAAAUGAUCCAGGCCUAGAUUACAUUUUAUGAGCAACUUAGAUUAUAACCUAAAGAAUACUUGGUGCCAAAUUAUGUUUUCAAAUAACAUUAAAGUUUUAGAAUUUGGAUGAACUAGAAGGAAGGUAAAAUUGUAAUUUUUGCCAUAUUUUCUAGAAAAAAAAAUGUCUUUUAGAGCAAAUUACAGUUAGGCCAACAAAAUCUUUGUUUUGUGAAACUUUAGAAAUACAUAUUUGCAUGUAAUUGAUGAAAACAUAGAAUGAGUUGUAAAUGAAGCAAUUCCAAGCUGGUUUGAAGGACCAGAGGUUGCAUUGAAAUCAGAAGUCAUAUACUCAGAGGCCUUCAGGAGCCAAAUGUGAAGACUCAAGAUGGUAGAUACUGUGUGAAUUAGAAAAUACCAAGCCCUGCCUAAAUGCAUUAAAAUUUAAUGUUUAAAAAUCCUAAAACCCACCAGCAGGUGUAUCUGGAGGGACAGUUUGUGGACUCUCCUCUAAAUUUUCUUUUAACACAUUUAUCUUCAUCAGACCCUUUUAGUUAGCUAGGGACUGUGUGAGAACCUUGAGAAAAUUGUCCAAGAGAGGGAGAUAAGUCACUCAAGGUCACCCAACAAGCCAGGCUGGUAAAGCCCAGGACAGCAGACUCUCUGUCUCCGAGAGCAAUCAUUAGGCCCUACUUCCUCUUCCCCAGUUGCGGAGGACACUGCUGCCUGGUGGGGUGGCACUGCCUGCCACUGUAGCACUUAGGAGUCUUCAGUGUUUUAACAAACCACAAUGUGUUUGGAGGUUUUCUUCCCUGCUUCCUGGUGCCAGUAUCUCAACACCACAUCCAUUGCCCCAGCCCUUUCUUGUUUUAUCUUUCCCUCUGAAAGCUACAACUCUAUAUUUUAUUUUAUUACUCUUUGUUUGGUCCAACAUGGCCCCAUUUCCUUUAUACUCAUAAAAAGGUAGAAUUUCAGCUUGUCUGGAAUAUCUCCUGGCCUUCACAAGGCACCAGAGUUAGAGACACCCAACAGAAAGUCGUAAUAAGAGAAGAUGUCACAGAAAUAGAAACAAAAGCAAAAGACUGCUUGAAGUCAGUAACAGACUGCACUAAGUGUCUGUGCUUGUUAACUAUUGUAAUCUCCAGGUUUAAAUCAUUCAUUUAUGUUAAUAAGAGCUGUCACUUAGCUCUUUCUCUGGGCCAGGUACUCUCCUGUUGUUUUUCACAUUAUCAUAAUAGUAACAGCACCAAUACUAUCAUUCCCCACUUUGUUGCUCAGGAAUCAAAUUUAGAGAAUUAAGUACUGUGACCACGGUUACACCCUAAUAAGCGGGAAGCCAGAAUUUAAACCCAGGUCUAGCAGACUUCACAGCCUCUUUCCUUAAUCUCUUCUCUCCUAGCUGCACUGAUUCCAUCUUGUAUUGGUGAAUAACAACACUGAUCCCCCUACAACUACCCCCACACAUGUACAGUAUGGCCUUGGGGCAAAGGAGUUUGCCUUUUGCAAAGAAGGUCUUGCUUUGUAUAGCCUGUAAAAUGCAAUGUACAGUGAGGGAAAGAAAGUCUAAGGGUAGCAGUCAAAUCUUCUGGCCUGAAACUGUACUUUUGGAAGGGAGAACUGUUAGACUUGCUUUAUCUUCUUUAUUCCAAGGCCAUAAAUAAGAAAAUCAACGAGAGGCAAAACCAUGUCUUCUUUUGCUAUAGCGUUAGAAUCCUGAAAGUCAGCCAGCUCUGACACUGAGUCUGUGAUUUAAUUAAACAUGUUGAAGGCUCUCCAACAGCUUGACGUCAGGCCAGCUUCAUAUUCUUGGAAAGGGACAACAGCAAAAGGAGCUUAUCUGUUUUAAAGUUCACUUACUGAGUUCAGCUGUCACGGCCACAGCAUACCAUUUGCCUUAUAAAAAUGGCCCACAACCUUCACAAUAUUUUAGGAUUCAUGGCAACUCAUUUACCUAGGGCUUAGCCACCUGAUAGCUUUACCUAUCCCUAUUUCCUGAACACAAAAUCUAAACCAGUGGUUUGACAAUGAGUAACUGAGACAGAACUAGAAAAAUCUAGAACCUCUGCUGAACCCAUCAAAAGUGACUGAGAAUUAAGAAGUAAGCAAACAAGGCUUCCAACCAAUUGAAAUAAAUACCAUGAAGCAAACGCAUAAGACAAAGGCCAUACAUCUAGUCAUCAGGCACCUCCUCAGAACCUAUUUGCUCUUCCUUCACACAUAUUUCUAACUGUAAAGGAAAGAAACAGACUUUUAGAGGAAACAAGAAGGAAAAAGGAGGACAGCAAUAGAGAAAAUGGAAAUUUUGAGUAGACUGCAAAGCUCCAAAGCCCUGAUAUAUGGGUUAUUUAGUGUCAAAAACAGUCUAUACACAUCUCAAUCUUUAAGAGCCUCACUGUAUCAUGGGACAAUAUUCUAUUUAAAAUGAUGACCCUGUGCACCAUACAUAAAAAAACUAUGCUUAGAAGACAAAAAUAUGUAUAUCAAACAUUUUAGAAAUAUUUACAUCCCAAUGGUUAAAAAAAAAAACUUUUAGGAAUUAAAAGGAAUAAACCUUUGACCAUCCAGAAUAUUUAGCUAAAUCAAACAGUGUAUAUCCCCCUAGCUGACUUUUAUUGUUUCAUGAGCCUCUGGUGUUCAGAGAGUUUUUUUCACAGCUUUGUAAGUGACUUUCAUGCUACAGUGCUUUGCAUAUAAUGGCAUGAACAGUGGAGGUGCCAACUUUCCAAUGUGAUGAAUAAAACUAAUAACUAGAAUACAGAUCAAAUUCUGUUACAACAAAUACUGCUACCAUAAAAGUCACUUAAGCAUCCCUGUUAGUUCUAAGCCCCUGUCGAUUGCCCAUUUAUUUUAGGCAAUAGUCAUUCAACAAAAUUGGAGCAUAAUAAAAAGAAACUGGACCUCAGCGCAAGUUGAGUGUUACACAAUUUAACCUGUAAUAACAGGUUCUCACUUGUAUUUCUCCAGCUCUUUGCUGUAAGAAGAAUAAACGUUAUGUAGAUAUAAUACCAGCGUGACAGCUUGUGGUUGGUGGUUUCUAGAAGAAAUAAUUCAGAAGCAAAAGACACAUGAAGUUAUGUGGCAGUUCCUCACUAGGGAAUUUGGUCUCCAGGGCCACUUUUGACCUUAAUCCAUGUUGGAGCCAUCAAUCAAAGAAUUGCUUGCAUCUAAUAAUGGUGUAAUGCCAAUACUAAGCCCUGGAACGAAGAUAGGAUUCAUUUCUCAUGGAUUAUUGAGCACUCUGGGGUAACCUGGCCCUGAUCUGAUGACGCUAAGAUUUAAAAACCCAGAUGCAUGUGACUAGAACUAUCUUUUCUCCCAUGAUGCACUGCUUUCAACACUGCAUGACUGUAAAAACAUGUGCCACGCUGAUUAUAUAUAGAGAUGGUCUAAAUCAGCUGCAUCCCAUUUGGUACCCAGGCAAGGAUUUUUCCAUACCUAUCUUUUUGCUGGUGGUAAUGAUGAGUUUUGUCACUUGCUAUAACAUUCUCUGUCCGUCUUUUUUCUUUUAUGUAAAUACUUUUGUGACUUCAUUGUAACCAGCAUUUUGUAAUACUCUUAACAGCAGAGGGGAUUAAAUCAUGAUUCACUUCUGAACAGUACAAUCAGCAGUAGGAAAACGAGGAGGGAGGGAGAGGGAAAUUGUCCACCACUUCCCAAUGAUAAUGCCUGGCUCGGACCCCAGAUUCACAUCAUACUUGAAGUUCAUAAAUUCUGGGCACUGCUCAGCUUGAGGAGGCAGGCAUUGCUCCUUCAUAUUUCAGGGUGAGACAAAUGCUCUGUUGAAGCCAUGCCACUACAGGAUACAUUCACCUCUGCUUGCUUUCCUCCCUAAGCCAGAGUGUAGUUAAACAUUUAUAUGUCCCAGGCCAGGAGAUCAAAUUAAGAGGAGGUUAGCUACUUUCCCUGGCUCUUAAAAACAUUUGAGUCCAAGUAUGGUUCUCUGGCUUGAGGGUGGCCAUUUGUUGCCUCACUGUUUUUAUUAGGACAUCUGGAGAUUAGAGGUGUUAAUUGGAAGUAACUUUUCUAUAUUUGGUUUCUCUCCACACAUUAUGAGACCUUUUAGACCCAGUUGGAUGGCUGUAUCCUAGUAUGAAAUUCAGCUUCUAAGUAGGAAGAACUAUGAUAGAGGAACAAGAUUGCUCUUUGACUUGGUGAUAGUAGGGCAAUAGGGAGUGUCAGUAGGGUAGUUUCAGGUGGGGAGGAUGACAAACCACUGAUAACAAUAAAAAUGGGUAUUUCUCAACACUCAAGCCAAUUUCCCAUUUGAUAACAAGUAGGUUCUGAUCUAUUUUCCCCAAAUUAAUAUUUUCCCUGGAAGAUUCUGACCUGUCUGAUCAAAUAAAGGCAUUCCUCUGAGAGUAUACCUAGCCCACUUGUGGCCAAAUUAUACUUGACUGUUAUGUACUCAAAACAAGCUUUCCUGUUAAUCUCUUUCUCUUACCUCUAUUAUGAGGACAAGACGUGGAAGAAUUAGGUCACCGGGGCAUCUGCCAUUGCAUAUGUUUAAGUGGUAUAAAGAAGCCAGGAUUCCUAGAAUGGUCUGUCUUUUGCCAUUUCUGGGACAAUGAGAAAAUCCAUCUGGAGUGUUUAUGCCCCUCUGAAUAGCCAAGUCAUGGGCUUGUUUGCUUUCAGUCACUGCCUUCAGAAAAAGACAAUUUUACAAUGACUUACUUCUAAUAAUCACUGAAACAGCCUCAUGAGGACAUGCAAAACUGCUGUCUAUCUUCAGACCUGGCCCAUUGUCAAAUGGCAGACUUGCAGAGCAAAUAAGGGACCUGGCCUAGUUCACAAGGCAGUCAGAAGUGAUCCAAAGUUCAGGCUCCCCCUCCCUUUUAUCACUCCACCCUGCCUCUACUCCUCCGCCUCCUAUUCUUCCGGCCUUUCCAUCUGGAAACCAUGAGCCUCAUGGAUUCCAGGCACAAAUUCUCAGAUUUCAGAUGUUUGGGAAAUUUCUCAGCUUGGGUCAUUCUUCAAGAGUAAGAAAUUGAAUUUGUGAGAAAAAAAAACAGCUGAGACUGUUUCACAGAAGAGAAAAUAAAUAAGGUGUGGUGCGUAUCCAUCCUCUUCCCAACUCAGCUCCAAAACCACACACAAUGUCUAACUUCAAAAAGAGUAUUUAGAUCCCCCCUGGGAAGGAACAGAAUGGAAAAACAAUCUCCACUCAUAAAAACACUUUUCUGCCUUCUACAGUAUAAACACAACUGGCAUCAGAUAAUACAAUGUAAUUGAUUUUAUGUGUGUAAUUGGGGAACAGAAGGGUCUCUAGAGGGUAGACCUAAGAGUAAUGGAAUGGAGUGAAAAGUAAAAUUUAGACUAAAUUGUUGGGAGGAAACUGUUAACAUUGUGAACCACUUGACCCUAGUGUUGCAUCUUCACAAAAAAGAGCAAUGUGCCGUCUUCUGUCUUUGGAAAAUGGGACAAGCUUGCUCCUGAUACUAGGUUUUAGAAGCAUACAGACUUGGUUUUAGUACUGGCUUUGUUCUUUACUAACUCUGAACAAUUAAAUGAGCAGAUGGUCUACAGGGCUUAGUACAGUGCCUGACACAUAGUAAGCACUUAGAAAUGGUAGCUUCUGACUGUUGUGCUGGAGUCCUGUUAGAGAUUCAGUAGAUGGAGCCACCUUCAUGUUGCCCCUCACUGAGCUGCUCUGCUCACCUCUAGAUGCUCCCCAUGGCUGUUUCAUAGCCCUCUGUACCACAUCCCCAUGUACUUUUUCAUAUCAACGGUAAGUACCUCAAAUUACCGUAUGUAUUUACUUGUUCAUAAGGUUGAUGUCUGUAACUCUUUGAAGGUUGUAUUAGUCGUUUGCUCCUAUAUUACUAAUGAUGACAAAGUCGCCUGACAGAGUAGAUGUUCAAAUUUAUGGACUUAAACUGACUGACAUCUUGAUAAUGCCCAUAUCCAGAGGUACUCCAGAUAUUAUAUCUUCAUGCAGAAAACUGAAAGAUACCUUUAGCUACAUCUACCCCAGAAUGAGUGUCCAAAGCAGGUGGCACCACCAAAAGGCACCUUCUUUUCCCAUGAAAAGAGGGAAGAGAGUUGAGAAGCCUCACUCCCAUCCCUGCUCUGCCACUGACAAGUUGUGUGGCAUUUGGCACAUCAUGUUCUCUCUCUACAUGCGCCUAAAAUGACGGGUAGGGUCAGAGACAUUGGAGGAUCUCUCUUUUCUCUUCCACCUCUAACACGGUAAGAUCUUAGCAAAGUAAAAAGGACAGUGAUAACAGAAAAAUUGUUCCUCUAAGAGUCCCAAGUCAUCUUUUUUCUCUCCGUGUGUGUUAGCAUUUGUGUGUGUCUGUGGGUGUGUAUGCAUGUGUGUGGAAGCUAUACAAGGAAAGCUGAAUCCAUAUGUAGACUUCAUGGAGACUAGUACUGCUCCAAAUGUGCACAAGCCAUGUGAUAUGGUUUGCCUCUGUGUCCCCACCCAAAUCUCAUGUUGAAAUGUAAUCCCCAAUGCUGGAGGUGGGACCUGGUGGGAAGAUUGGAUCAUGGGGGAGUUUUCUCAUGAUUUAACAACAUCCGCCCUUUGUUGUCAUGAUAGUGAGUUCUUGUGAGAUCUGGUUGUUUAAAAAUAUGUGACACCUCCCCCCACCUUCCUUCUGCUCUGGCCAUGUAAAGUGCUCACUCCCCCUUUGCCUUCCACCAUGAUUGUAAGUUUCCUGAAGCCUCCCUAGAAGCUGAGCAGAUGCCAGCAUCAUGCUUGCUGUGCAGCCUGCAGAACUGUGAGCCAAUUAAACCUCUUUAUGAAUUA